CUCCGUCUGAAAACCUUGGCCGAAAGGGUUGUAGACAUGGCGGCCAUCAGGAUGGGAAAACUGACAACCAUGCCUGCAGGUCUGAUAUAUGCAUCUGUAAGUGUACAUGCAGCCAAACAAGAGGAAUCCAAAAAGCAGCUAGUGAAACCAGAGCAGCUCCCCAUAUAUACUGCACCACCGCUCCAGUCUAAAUAUGUUGAAGAGCAGCCUGGUCAUUUACAAAUGGGCUUUGCUUCCAUCCGCACUGCAACUGGUUGUUACAUUGGCUGGUGCAAGGGUGUUUAUGUCUUUGUGAAAAAUGGGAUAAUGGAUACAGUACAAUUUGGAAAAGAUGCUUAUGUCUAUCUGAAGAAUCCUCCUCGAGAUUUUCUUCCGAAAAUGGGAGUUAUUACAGUUUCAGGAUUGGCGGGCUUGGUUUCAGCGAGAAAAGGUUCCAAGUUUAAGAAAAUUACUUAUCCUCUGGGACUGGCCACUUUAGGAGCAACUGUUUGCUACCCAGUUCAGUCCGUAAUAAUUGCUAAGGUAACAGCAAAAAAGGUAUAUGCUACAAGCCAGCAAAUUUUUGGAGCAGUUAAAUCAUUGUGGACAAAAAGCAGCAAAGAAGAGUCACUCCCUAAACCUAAAGAAAAAACUAAGCUAGGAUCCUCUUCCGAAAUAGAAGUACCUGCAAAAACAACUCACGUCUUGAAACACUCAGUGCCCUUGCCAACAGAACUCAGCUCUGAAGCAAAGACCAAAUCAGAAUCCACUUCAGGUUUGUUGGGUGCAACCCAGUUUAUGCCUGACCCCAAGCUCAUGGAUCACGGGCAGUCCCACCCAGAAGAUAUAGAUAUGUACAGCACUAGAAGCUGAAGUAGACUGCAUGCAGAGACUACACAGAAAACUACAAGAUGUGUGGCGUUGCAAAUAAUGAUGAAAAUAAAUCAUGUAAUGGGUAACUGAUACAUAGAGUAUUACCUAAACCAAGUUUCUCCCUUACAUUUCCAAAUAUGCCAUUUGAUAAAUUACAUAAGUGGUUAACACACAAACUGUGAAUGCAGUGUAAACAAUAUUAAAUGAUUGAUGAGGAGACUUAGGUAGAAGUAUUAGCUUGCAUUUGAUGACCUUUAAGGGCACUUAAAAAAAAAUGAAGACAUGAAUUCUAGUGAGAUUAAAAUCUAAAAAUACAUAUAUAUAUAUGUAUGUAUAAAUACAUACAUAUUUAUACAUGUAUAAAUACGUAUUUAUACAUAUAUGUAUAAAUACAUAUACAUAUAUGUAUAAAUACAUAUACAUAUUUAUACAUAUAUGUAUAAAUACAUACAUAUUUAUACAUAUAUGUAUAAAUACAUACAUAUUUAUACAUAUAUGUAUAAAUACAUACAUAUUUAUACAUAUAUAUGUAUAAAUACAUACAUAUUUAUACAUAUAAACAUAUAUUUCUGCUCUAGCUUUCCCAGAUUAAUGCUAGUUAAAUUAGAAUGGUGUAUGGAAAGGUGUGUUUCCCUCUGUUUUUUUUUUUUUUUUUUUUUUUUUUUUUCCCAUUUCCUAGAGCUGGAAUAAAAUAUCCAUGUUUUAUGGGACUUGAGCUUGGCUUUGUCCCUUGGUUUUGUUAAUGUUAAUUCCUCUUAAAUAUCUAAAAACAUCUCUACCUAUUUGAGAGGGCCAUAUGCUACACAGGCUUCCUAAUACUGCUUAGCAAUCCUUCUACUGGUUCCUAAGUGGUUUACUAUUGUGUUCCCUGGAAGAGGUAUUACAAACGUUUUAUUCUUCUCAAGCCUCUUAGAACUGUCAAAGUUGACUGUGCCUCCUAUUUCAUAGAGAAAAAACUAAAUUAUUAGAUAUGACCAUUCCCAAAACUUCUUCCCAUCUACCUUCAAGACUUACCUCUUUUCAGCCAUGCAUCCCCCUUUUCUAAGACAUGCUUCUCUUUGUGUUCUUGACCUCAUUCCUUCCCAUCUAAGACCAUAUUCCACCCUGUUUAAUUUCUAGUCUUCGGUUUCUCUUUUUACAGUGAGCAAAUUAGAAGAAUAGGUUAGAAGAAUAGGGUAGUAGAUACUGUAGUUUCUUUCCUCCACCUCUACAUAGCUGCAGGUCUUCUCUGUCUUAAAUCAACAAUAACAAAACAAGACAAAAACCUUUCCUUAACUUGGCCUCUUCCCUUGAACUAUUUUUUCUCUCUCCUUCCUAUAAUUGUUAUACUUCUUUAAAAAGUAAUUGUUACUUUUUGACAAAAGUAAAUAUUGUCCCUUUUUUCCCUACUUUCAAGUCCUCUCUGUCUUGUGACAUUCUGGCCUCCAUACCUGCUUAAUUUUUUUUGAGAUGGGGUCUUGCUCUGUUGCCCAGGCUGGAGUGCAGUGGCACAAACACAGCUCACUGCAACCUCCACCUCCCAGGAUCAAGCAAUCCUCCCAUCUCACCCUCCCAAGUAGCUGGGACUAUAGGCACCCGCCACCAUGCCUAAUUUUUUGUAUUUUUGGUAGUGACAGGGUUUCACCAUGUUGUCCAGGCUGGUCUCGAACUCCUGAGCUCAAGCAUCUGUCCGACUCAGCCUACCACAGUGUUGGGAUUACAGGCGUGAGCCACCGCACCCAGCCCCUACUUGAAUUUUUAUGUCAUUAUUGACUCUUCACCACUCUCUCCUUGAGACUCACUUAUCCCUUUGCUCUCUAUUUUUCCUGCUUUUGUUAUUCUUCAUUUUUCUUCUCUUGCUCUGAAUCCCUUAAAUGCUGAGGCUGCUCAAGUUUCAUCCCUAGUCCUAUUUUCUCAUUCUAUAUGCACACUCAUUUUUCAUUUAACAGACUUCACUGGCUUCAGGCACCAUUUGUUUUAUUAUUCAUAUUUUCAACCCCCAUAUCUCUCUAGUGCUGUAGACCUUUAUUUCUACUUACUAGUUAUAUUCACCUAACAUCCCAUAGAUAUGCCAAUGUCAAUGUGCCUAAAACAAAAUUGUCUCUACCUCCCGCUCCUUCAAAUCUAUUCUGUCUUCUCUAAUCCUAUAAUUACUCUCCCUCAAGUCAUCAUCAUCACUUUUCUGGGUUACUGUAAUAGCCUUCAGGCUAAUUUGCUCACUGUCAAUCUUGCUGUCUCUCAUUUCAGAAUAUGUUCUGCUUGCAGGUGACAGUAAACUAGUUAAACAAAUAUUUAAUAUUAGCUUAAGCAAAAAAAAAAAAAAAGGCCUAUCCUAUUUAUAGCCUAGAAUUAGGCAGUAUAGGGUUGGGACAGUGGCUCAUUGGUGCUAUCAAGGACGUAGACUUUUUCUCUUUCCACUCUGUCCUCUACAGCAUGCUGGUUUGUCACCUCAUGGUCACAAGAUGUCUGCUGUACCUCCAGGGAGCAGAUACACAUUCAAAGUAGGAAAUAGCAGAUAAAAAUGUACACAAGAUGCGUCUGACUCCCUUUUACCAGAAAAGUAAAUGCUUUCUUAGAAUCUCCUCAGAAGACCUCUGUGUAUAUCUCAACCAGUACUUGUCAUAUAGCCACACACUUAGCUCAAGGAAGAUAGGGAAUAGGGAAAUCAUGUUUCUUUUCCCCUGUGGUGAGGAAGGCAAGGGGUAAGGGGUUGGGAACAGGUGCUGAAUUAAAGCUAACAUACAGUAUCUACUACCCUAUUCUUCUAACCCAUUUGUCUAUUAUGAUAUAGUUGUCUUGACAACUAUAAUGAAUAGCUGUCUUUCUGAAAUCUUUAGUGGCUCAUCAUUGCCUGCAGAAUCAAAACUCCUUAGUCUGAUAUACAAGGCCCUUCAUAUCUGAUUCCAGCUUACCUUCUAAUCCUAUCUUCCCUCUCCUUACCCACCCUACUGCUAAUGUGUAUUAUAUUGUCUUUAUGACAUACCAUUUGUUUCUUGAACAUGCUUUGCUCAUUAUUGCCUCUUUCUCUGCCUGUGCUAGUGUGUCCUCUUAGAAUGUUCUUCCAUCUUAUCCUGCUCUACAUUCUAACUUCUACCCAUCCUACAAGUCCAAUUCCAGUGUCAUGUUCCCUUUCUCAAUCCUCCAGGGUAGAAUUUAGAUGUUCUGUCUUUUAGAGAUAGGUAUUGCUAUGUUGCCCAGGCUGGUCUCAAACUCAUGGCCUCAAGCGAUCCUCCCACCUCAGCCAACCAGACAUGAGUGACUGUGCUCAGCCUUUUUUAAAAAAAUGAAGGUAUUUGGUAUGGCCGGGUAUGGUGGCUCACACCUAUAAUCCCAGCACUUUGGGAGGCCAAGGUGGGUGAAUCACCUGAGGUCAGGAGUUUGAGACCAGCCUGACCAACAUAGUGAAACCCUGUCUCUACUAAAAACACGCAAAAAGUGCAAAAUUAGCUAGGCGUGGUGGCUCAUGCCUGUAAUUCCAGCUACUUGGGAGGCUGAGGCAGGAGAAUCACUUGAAUCCGGGAGGUGGAGGCUGCAGUGAGCCGAGAUCGUGCCAUUGCACUUCAGCCUGGGCACAAGAACAAAACUCAGUCUCAAAAAAUAAAUAAUAAAAAAUAAAGGUAUAUAAUAUGUCUUAGAUUUGAUGAAAUAUGAGUGUGUUUGAGAUCUGAUCCAAGGUUUUAAAAAAUUCAUUUCAAAUCCUGGAGAUAAAUUCUGAGGAGCUUACUUAUGAAAAACUAGCAAGUGAUAGCUGGUAUUUACAGAUAUGGUACUUUACACAAUUUAUGUAAUUAAUAUUUUCUCACAGACAAGGUUCCUUGUGGAUAUCACUGAAUAAUUUUUGUGUAGUUUCUAUGCCCAUGAAGUGCCUGGUAGGUAGUAGGAACUCACACGUUCUGCUAUGCUGGUUGCAGCACAGGACACAAAAGUUAGAAUUAUUUCAAAGGACUUAUACUCUACUAGGAAAGAGAGAAACAUAGAAAUAUAGUGUUGUAUGUGGUAUCUUCCCUAAGAUAAGUACAACCAAAGAGCUAUGGAUGUUCAGAGAUAGAAUGUAGUACUGGGAUGAUGUCAAGGAGGCAGUGGUACUUAAGCUGCUCAAGGUAGGGAAGCAGUUUACUUGCUAGUUUUUCAUAAGUAAGCUCUUCAGAAUUUAUCUCCAGUAUUUGAAAUGAAUUUUUUUAAACCUCAGAUCUGAAUAUAUUCAAACACCCAUAUUUCAUCAAAUCUAAGGCAUAUCAUAUACCUUUAAUUUAAAAAAAAAUGCUGAGCAGAGUUGCUUAUGUCUGGGAGGCUGAAGUGGGAGGAUUGCUUGAGGCCAAAAGUUUGAGACCAGCCUGAGCAACAUAGCAAGAUCCUGCCUCUAAAAACAAACAAACAAAAAAUGCUGCCAGUUGAUCAUUACAUUUAUCCCGACAUCAGAUAUGUCAAAUUGUGAAAAGCACCUUAAUUUUGAUGAAAUAUGAUAGGUAAAAAAUAGCGCAAAGCUAAGUAUAAGUGACUUUUAAAUUAUCUGCUCUUUUGGAUUAUCACUACUGCUACUAGCCGUUAGAAUAUUGGUUUGGAUAAUGGAAAGUUGACUAGAGCUACAAAAUCUGUUUCAAAAUAAAAGAUCUGCUCAAACAAGAAUGUGAUGAUCACUUGCUGUAUUGUACAACAAAGUCAAACUGCUGUUAGACUCAGGUGACAGUCAAAUGUUGGAGGCUGUGUUGGGAUGAGUUGUUACAAAGCCUCUUUCAUUCUUCCCAUGCCAUGUCCAGGAGUUCUUCUCUGUUAAACCUGAAGAGAUGCCAGCCCUCCUCAGAGGAAAGGUCUAAAGCCCCUCGACUAGUAUAGUAGUUGAUAGAAGCCUGGUUCCAAAUGACGACAAGAAAGUGCAUGCAGUUACAUUGAGUUGUGAUGGCUAUCUGUUUAAAAACAAACAAGCAAAUAUUACUUUCAUUUGAAAGUAUAAUCUUCGUUAACACAUAUAUUUUAUUGAAGGUCUACUCUAUGCAAGACACUAUGUGUGAAUAAUACUUCCAAAUAUAGUAGUUACCUUUUGAACUUUUCUAUAGCUGUAAAAAGAAAAAAGUCUCACUGUUCUGAGCUUUAAAGCCCUCUUUAAAAUCUCAAAACUGAUUUGCAAAGCCUUUAUCAUACAGAAAAGGUGUACCUAAAAGAACACAUGUUCUCAUAUGUUUCCAAAAUACAAGAAGAUCUUGCUUUUAUAGUCUUGUAAUAUUCAUACUGUGAGCCUGUGUUUUUGAAUAAAAAUGCUUUCUAAUCUCCCUCCUUCUUACUUUCCCUUGAUAGCAAAAAGGGUGUAUAGUGUGGUUGUGGAUUAUAUAUAAAUCAAUUUUAAUUGACUAUAAUUCAUAUACUGUAUAUGAUCAUCUGAUUUGAAAAUCCAGUUUAAUUUGGGUAGAAAUUUGAAGUAUAUGUUGGGGUUAUGUUCAAAUGGUGAGAUUAAUGAUUUAAUUUAUGCCCUGUGAAUAUUUAUUAAGAAAAGGUUAAUGUAUAGAAUAUCAAUACUAAUUGUAAUACAUACCUGACUUAGCCUCUUCAGCAUUUCAGCUCCAAUACCUAGGCCUUUUAAAUAGACAAUGCAAAGUGAAAACUGCAAAUUUCACUUAACUUGUUAUUUGCUUUAGUUUAAAAUAAAUAAUAUCUAAAACUCUG